GCGGUGGCGCGAGUUGGACUGUGAAGAAACAUGGCGGCCGCGACGUUGACUUCGAAAUUGUACUCCCUGCUGUUCCGCAGGACCUCCACCUUCGCCCUCACCAUCAUCGUGGGCGUCAUGUUCUUCGAGCGCGCCUUCGAUCAAGGCGCGGACGCUAUCUACGACCACAUCAACGAGGGGGUGAGGGCCUGUGCCAUCCCUGACCUUGGACCCGCCUGAGGGGUGACAGUGGAGUAGAGAAGCUGUGGAAACACAUCAAGCACAAGUAUGAGAACAAGUAGUUCCUUGGAGGCCCCCAUCCAGGCCAGAAGGACCAGGUCCACCCAGCAGCUGUUUGCCCAGAGCUGGAGCCUCAGCUUGAAGAUGAUGCUCAAGGUACUCUUCAUGGACCACCAUUCGCUGUUGGCAAGAAACGGCUUUACUUACAAAACAGACUCUUUACCUUCUGCUGUGUUUGAAGUAUGUUUAGUCAGCAUGCUCAGGAAAUAAAUGUGAAUUGCCCUUGAGACCUGCUUCUACAUUGGUUGCUUUGUUAACUCUACCUGAUCUUCACUUGUCAGUAAUUUGAGACCACUUCAAAGCCCUCUGCAAACACCCCAAAGGCAGAAUCUGCUAUUUUGAGUUUUCCAUUAACUUCCAAAGAAUUCUGGUUUUCAAAACAGGAGCCAGAGUUGGAGAUAUUACAGUCAACUUUGGCUUCUAAGCCAGUAAUUCCAUUCUUAAAUACCUCACUGUCUUGGCCAUGGGGAAGCACUAUGGCCUCAGCUGGGGGAAAGACCCUGGCCUAGGGGUCUUAGCCACUCCCCACCCUAGGGUAUAGUUCAGGGGUAUCCAAUCCUUUGGCUUCCCUGGGCCAUGUUGGAAGAAUUGUCUUGGGCCACACAUAAAAUACAGUAACCAUAGCUGAUGAGCUAAAACAAAAAACAAUGGUUUGUGCAAAAAUCUCAUAAUGUUUUAAUAAAGUUGAAGAAUUUG